GACCAGAGUCUCUCCUCACUCCUGGAGGGGACAGCGCAAGACCGCACCCUCGAAAGCCAGGCCAGACAGGCAGCAGCCACAGCCAGGACCGCUCCACCCCUUGGGGCUCUCCUCAGGGAAGUGCCUUCUAAGCUUCCAAUGAAUUCCGGCUGUGGAGUGUGGCUGCCCCGGUCUCCCCAGUCUCCCGCUGUAGCUGAAUUCCAGCCUGGCCCGCAGCUAGCCCUGUCUGCAGCUCCAAGCGUGCUGCCUGGCAGUCCCCACCUAGGGCACGCUGCCACGCCGCCGUUACCUGGUCCAAGUGCCCGGGAGGCUCCGCCUGUCGGCUUCGCUCUGCAGCUGCAUCUCUGAUCUGUCCUGCAGGCUCAGGCUCUGACACCUCCAUUCUCUGUCCCCAAGCGCCAUGAGAGGCCUUCUUUGCUGGCCCGUGUUGCUGCUCCUUCUUCAGCCCUGGGAAACCCAGCUCCAGUUGACAGGUCCCAGGUGUCACACUGGGCCCCUGGAUCUGGUGUUCGUGAUUGACAGCUCCCGCAGCGUGCGCCCUUUCGAGUUCGAGACCAUGCGGCAGUUCCUCAUGGGCCUCCUCCGAGGCCUGAACGUGGGUCCCAACGCCACGCGCGUUGGCGUGAUCCAGUAUUCGAGUCAAGUGCAGAGCGUCUUCCCUCUCCGCGCGUUCUCUCGCCGCGAGGACAUGGAGCGCGCCAUCCGCGACCUGGUGCCUCUGGCGCAAGGCACCAUGACGGGACUGGCAAUCCAGUACGCCAUGAACGUGGCCUUCAGUGUGGCCGAGGGCGCGCGACCGCCAGAGGAGCGCGUGCCGCGUGUCGCUGUCAUCGUGACAGACGGGCGGCCCCAGGACCGCGUGGCCGAGGUGGCGGCACAGGCGCGCGCCCGCGGCAUUGAAAUUUACGCGGUGGGGGUGCAGCGCGCGGACGUGGGCUCCCUGCGCGCCAUGGCAUCGCCCCCGCUAGACGAGCACGUCUUCCUCGUAGAGUCCUUCGACCUCAUCCAGGAGUUCGGCCUGCAGUUCCAGAGCCGGCUGUGUGCCAUUGAUCUGUGUGCUGAAGGGACCCAUGGAUGUGAGCACCACUGCGUCAAUUCCCCAGGCUCCUAUUUCUGUCACUGCCAAGUUGGCUUUGUACUCCAGCAGGACCAGAGGAGCUGCAGGGCCAUUGACUACUGCAGCUUUGGGAACCAUAGCUGUCAGCAUGAGUGUGUUAGCACCCCUGGUGGGCCACGGUGCCACUGCAGAGAGGGCCAUGACUUGCAGCCUGAUGGGAGGAGCUGUCAGGUCCGGGACCUUUGCAAUGGCGUGGACCAUGGCUGUGAGUUCCAGUGUGUGAGCGAGGGCCUCUCCUACCGCUGCCUGUGCCCCGAGGGGCGGCAACUUCAGGCAGAUGGCAAGAGCUGCAACCGGUGCCGGGAAGGCCACGUGGACCUUGUUCUGCUGGUUGAUGGCUCCAAGAGCGUGCGUCCACAAAACUUCGAGCUAGUGAAGCGCUUCGUGAACCAGAUUGUGGACUUCCUAGAUGUGUCCCCCGAGGGCACGCGGGUGGGGCUGGUGCAGUUCUCGAGCCGCGUGCGCACCGAGUUCCCUCUGGGUCGCUACGGCACCGCAGCCGAGGUGAAGCAGGCGGUCCUGGCCGUGGAGUACAUGGAACGCGGCACCAUGACAGGGCUGGCGUUGCGGCACAUGGUGGAGCACAGCUUCUCCGAGGCGCAGGGUGCACGGCCCCGUGCCCUUAACGUGCCUCGUGUUGGCCUGGUCUUCACGGAUGGCCGCUCCCAGGAUGACAUCUCGGUGUGGGCAGCGCGCGCCAAGGAGGAAGGCAUCGUCAUGUACGCCGUGGGCGUGGGCAAGGCGGUGGAGGCGGAGCUGCGCGAGAUCGCCUCGGAGCCAGCGGAACUGCACGUGUCCUAUGCCCCGGACUUCGGCACCAUGACGCACCUGCUGGAGAACCUCAGAGGCAGCAUCUGUCCAGAGGAGGGCAUCAGCGCAGGGACAGAGCUUCGGAGCCCAUGCGAAUGCGAAAGCCUCGUGGAGUUCCAGGGCCGCACGCUGGGGGCGCUCGAGAGCCUGACGCUGAACCAUAUCCUUUGGGGCUGGUGGCGCGGGCUGGAGGGAAAGUGAAGGGACCUCGGCGAACCCCAACGGCCUCCUUAACCGCUCACUGGCCCAGCUGACGGCGCGCCUGGAGGAUCUGGAGAACCAGCUGGCCAACCAGAAGUGAGGGCCACGGACGGCCCAGACCCGGGCUGGGGCGCGGCACCACGGACGGUGCCCCUUGCGCGCCAUCGGUGCGCCGGGGCCAGGCAGAACCUGGGCCCGUCCGGCUUGGGCUGUCGGGGCGGAGGCGCUGGCGGGCUUCCGGCAUUGAGCUGAGUUGGCCUCGCCCGGACCAUUAGGCGGACUGCGGCGUCAGGGGGAUAGCGGGUGGUGAGGGAAGGGGCACGUGCUAGACCGGCACGCCCUCGCCGCGUGCUGCGCUCAGUUCUUUGUUGGAUUUCUUGUUUGUGUUCUUAAAAAAAUAAAAAAAACUGAUUUCCA